ACGAGCCUUUCCGGUGCUAUGCCCCGGAAGCGGAAGUGCGAUCUUCGGGCUGUCAGAGUUGGUCUGUUACUCGGUGGUGGCGGAGUCUACGGAAGCCGUUUUCGCUUCACUUUUCCUGGCUGUAGAGCGCUUUCCCCCUGGCGGGUGAGAGUGCAGAGACGAAGGUGCGAGAUGAGCACUAUGUUCGCGGACACUCUCCUCAUCGUUUUUAUCUCUGUGUGCACGGCUCUGCUCGCAGAGGGUGAGAGCGGGUAUUUCUCAGACGUUUGAUCAGUCCCCGGGAGGAAGGGCCCCGGGGUCCCCUGUGCCACCAGGGGAAAGAUCGCGAGCCUUACUUGCUUGAGAGGCUCAUCUACUCCACUUCAGGGAAUCUCUGGGCAACUCGUGAACAGGAGCAGGAGGGGAGUAUGGAGUCGAUUGCCGAGUUUUCUUUGGUCUCAGGCAUAACCUGGGUCCUGGUUUACAGGACAGACAAGUACAAGAGACUGAAGGCAGAAGUGGAAAAACAGAGUAAAAAAUUGGAAAAGAAGAAGGAAACAAUAACAGAGUCAGCUGGUCGACAACAGAAAAAGAAAAUAGAGAGACAAGAAGAGAAACUGAAGAAUAACAACAGAGAUCUAUCAAUGGUUCGAAUGAAAUCCAUGUUUGCUAUUGGCUUUUGUUUUACUGCCCUAAUGGGAAUGUUCAAUUCCAUAUUUGAUGGUAGAGUGGUGGCAAAGCUUCCUUUUACCCCUCUUUCUUACAUCCAAGGACUGUCUCAUCGAAAUCUGCUGGGAGAUGACACCACAGACUGUUCCUUCAUUUUCCUGUAUAUUCUCUGUACUAUGUCGAUUCGACAGAACAUUCAGAAGAUUCUCGGCCUUGCCCCUUCACGAGCCGCCACCAAGCAGGCAGGUGGAUUUCUUGGCCCACCACCUCCUUCUGGGAAGUUCUCUUGAACUCAAGAACUCUUUAUUUUCUAUCAUUCUUUCUAGACACACACACAUCAGACUGGCAACUGUUUUGUAGCAAGAGCCAUAGGUAGCCUUACUACUUGGGCCUCUUUCUAGUUUUGAAUUAUUUCUAAGCCUUUUGGGUAUGAUUAGAGUGAAAAUGGCAGCCAGCAAACUUGAUAGUGCUUUUGGUCCUAGAUGAUUUUUAUCAAAUAAGUGGAUUGAUUAGUUAAGUUCAGGUAAUGUUUAUGUAAUGAAAAACAAAUAGCAUCCUUCUUGUUUCAUUUACAUAAGUAUUUUCUGUGGGACCGACUCUCAAGGCACUGUGUAUGCCCUGCAAGUUGGCUGUCUAUGAGCAUUUAGAGAUUUAGAAGAAAAAUUUAGUUUGUUUAACCCUUGUAACUGUUUGUUUUGUUGUUGUUUUUUUUUCAAGCCAAAUACAUGACAUAAGAUCAAUAAAGAGGCCAAAUUUUUAGCUGUUUUAUGUACAAGGAGAGAUCUGUUUCAUUUUGUUUUGCCGUAUUUCUAGAUAUAAGUUUUAGCAUGGGCCAGGAAGGACUAAAAUAAAAGUUUUUAAGGUACUGUACUUUUUGCCAUACUUGACUCAUAUACUCAAAAUACAGAGUUGUCUUGGUGUAGGAAUUGGAAAGCAAGAGUGGAAAGGAACGUAAUAACUCGUUGGAGUUUAAAAAUGAGGGUCUUGGCAAGUAACACUGAUGUCUGAAAAAAAAUUAAAUAUAAAUAAAUAAAUAAAAAUGAGGGUCCUCAGCUGUUCUCUUCAUAUCCUAUUACAGUCUCUCAGAUUCUUGUGGGGGCACUCUUAGAUCUCCCUUGGAGACAAGGUUAUAGUUAUAUGUUGUUAAUCUCGCAGAGCUUCCUUUUAGUCACAAUAGCCUUCAUUUUCUGCCAUGCCCCUUCAUAAGGGAGAAGGAUGUUUGUACCAUGAUCCUCCCCGCAUAAUCUAUGGAAUUAGGAGUCCUGUGUGGAGUCUUAUCAAUAAAUAUGCACAUUCAUCAAAUGUCUACUUAAAUGUGAGUAUUCUACCAGUGAGAAAAAACACAUAAUUUUCAAGGUAAUCAUUGUUAAACCAACAGCAAACUUCUUUCUUAUCAGCACCAUAAAGUCCAGAAGACAGUAGAAAAGUAUCUUCAAAGUGCUGAGGAAAAUAAGUAUCAACUUAGAAUUUUAUGUACAAUAUUGGAGGCAAAAUAAAGACAUGUUUAGACAUACAAAACUAAGAGAGUUGAAUUAUUAAAGGUUAUAUUCCAAGGACAAAAAAGAGGAUCUGCCCAAGGUGAAGGUAUGGCAUACAAGAAACAAUGGUCAACAGAGAAAUAAAAUAUAUGGAUGAAUAUAUGGAUAAAUUUGAGUGUUUUAUGGAUUAUCUAAUUUAAGGAUUAUCCCAAGACAGCCCUACAAGGUAAUUACUGUUCUUACCUUCAUUUAACAGAUGAGGAAACUGGGGCAGGGGAGGUUAGUAACUUGCUCUGCAUCACAGAGCUAUUGAGUGGCAGUCAGGAUUUGAAUUCAACCAGUGUAAAGCCUAAUAGUCCAGGCUGUCAAGCUCUAUAUUACAGCCUCCUCAUGGGUAUGUGGUGAUUCUCUUCUCAUCCCAUCUCCUCAACUAGAGUGUGUGAGCUCUCUAAAGUUGGACUUUGUCUUUUUUUUUGUUCUCCUUAUUACAAAGUAGUCAACGUGGGUGGAAACACAGCAGGAGCUCAAUAAAAGCAGAUGAAAGGGAACAGAAGUCCCUAUUCUGAGACUAGUUUUAUCAGAAGGAUGUCUGAUAAUGGAUGGUAAUGACUUUUAAUGGUCUUUUCUCCAUAUCAUUGACCACUCUAAGCAAAAUAAUAAUUCGAAUGAUAAUGAAGAAAAUGAUGCCCAUGAUAACAAUAAUGACAAAUAUGAAAUGGCUAAAAUAAAACAUGAAACCAUCCUCAAAAUUCUGCCAUCACCUUUUUAAAGUGAGAAUAUAUAGCACACUCUAUCACUCAUACCCUGAGGCUUUGAAGUUGGUGCUUUCUAAUCAGACUUCUUAUGGACCAGGUUUUCAUAUACAAAUUAUGUUUCCAUGGUAAGGAAUAAAUAAGAGGGAGAAGUUAAAAAGGAGAGAUUACAUCUAUUCACCCUAUUCAUUAAAAUUUUUUUAAAUUUUUUUCCAAAUAUGUUCUGCUUAUGUAUAUUCACUCUAUUCUUAAAAGCACAAUAACAAAGAUAUAUUACAGAGGAAAUAAAACUAUCACAAGAAUUAAAUUCAAGGAGUUAUUAAGGGCUACUGCAGCCUCACAAUUAGUUUUUUAAAAUUUCUUGUCCUGAAGAAAUUUCAAGACUAGUUAUUUGGAUGACACUCUAGGUCCACAGCAUCACCAGAUCAUUGGAGAUGACAUUUCAAGACAGGCCUCUGAACAUCUCUCAUAACACAUAAUUUGGUUAUUUUCCCUAUGUAAGAUGGAUUGUCUCCUGUCUAGGGAAGAAAAACAGCCAUUACUAAUAUCUGCAUUAGUCUACUCAGGUUGCAAUCAUAAUAUGCUAAAGUAGUAAACUUUUAAAAAUGACAGUAAACCUGAGUUUAUUAACAGGUUACAUUCUAAAAGCUAAGCUAGUUUGGAAAUUGGAAAGCAAAUGUGUGUAGAUAUUCAUAUGUCCUUGACCAGACUGGGCCUUUCUCUUCCCAGGUAAGUCAUUCUCUCCAAUGGGGCCAGUUACUUAAAAUUACAUCAGACAAUUGAUAGAGCUUCUAGAUCCCCCUUCUAAAACAAAAGCAUUUUGCCACAAACUAGGAUGGAGUAGGUUUUUUUCAGACUAUUUAUACUUAUUUUAUGUAUUUCAAUACUGCCCUUUAAGUAAAAGUACUAUAUACUUUCUCUUUUUUUAGAUUAAUUCUGCUUAAGUCAGUCUUUUAAUUUAUUCUAGUUUGAGUUUUUAAAAAAUUUUAGAAUGAAAAAUCUCAAAAAUAUACUAUUAUGUAUAUACACUAUUUUAUAUAUAUAUAUAUAUAUAUAUAGAGAGAGAGAGAGAGAGAGAGAGAGAGAGAGAGAGAGAAAGAGAGAAUAAAGAACACCUAGGUAACCCAUCCUCCACCUUCGACAAUUAUCAGCUCCUAGCUAAUUUGUGUCAUCUGUAACCCCACCUGCUUCUGCCCUUUCUGUAUUAUUUUGAAGCAAAUCUUAUCAUUUAUCUGUAAAUAUUUCAGGACUUUAAAAAAUAUGUGUAAUCUGAAUACCAUUUUUACACCUAAGAAAAUGGACAAUUCCUUAAUAUAAUGUGUUGUCUAUAGAUGUCAAAAAUUUUUGCAGUUUUUUGGAAUCAGGAACCAAGUAAGGUACUGAAUAUUGCAGUUAGCUGAUACACAUCCUAAAUUUCUUCAAUUGUUGUGGUCCUCAAACUAGAGUGUAUCAGAAUCACUAGAGCCUUGUUAGAACACAAACUGCUGGGCCCCACCCCAGAGCUGGUGAUCUGUAAGUCUGCUGUGGAGUCUGGGAAUUUGCAUCUCUAACAAAUUCCCAGGUGAUGCUGAAGCUGCAGGUUUGGGGUUCACUCACCUAUUGGUUCAUCAGCAUCUCUCUGCCCUCUUACAAUAUAUUUGUUGAAGAAGUUGUGUUGUUUACCUUGUAGAGUUUUUCUUAGUUUGGAUUUUGGUGAUAGCAUGCUGGUUUUUUCAUACUAUUGGUUGUCUCUGUAAUGCGAGCAGCUUUUGAUCUAUUAAUUAAUGAGAUAUUAAAAGUGAUGGUAUUCUAA